AAAAAGUUCGCGCUGCUGGUCCCGCGCGGGCGGCCCCUGGGCUUUGUGUCCACCAGGACAGCGGGCCGGGCUCCCUGCAGGCGCGGGCGGCGCCGAACGGUGCUCAGCAACCACCCGGACAGGGCCAGGCCGUUUUCUCCCGCUCAGGCAUUAGUCGUUGGCUGUGGGCCGCCGCGGGAAGUUGAGGCCUACCACGGAGGAGGCUGCUGAGGUGGAUCUCAGGGGAUCCGCAAGGGCUCCCUCACCCUUGCCGGGACCCUGGGAACCCGAAACAAAAUCCUACGCCACCAGCCCGCCGAAUGCGCCCCCUCGGCCGGGGGUCCUGGGUCUUCAGAGAAGAACUCGGCCGAAUGCGGUCAGAAAGCCCGCGAACCGCCUGGACCUGCAGGCCCCGCCGCUUGGAGCUCCCGCCUUUCCCGACCGAGCCCGUGUCUGCUCGUGUGUCUCACUGAUGUCUUAGGUCUCAAAAAAAAAAGAAAAGAAAAGGUUUUUAGUAGACAGAAGAGAAAUGGGGCCGUGGGUUCGUGGUCCCAGGGGGAAACUGACGUCGCAUGAGGUCGUCGUCCCUCAGCUUGAGCUCAGCGGAACAUAAGCUUGCAGAGGUGGAAACCACGGAAGGUUUGGGUGUCUUGGAGCUCUCUGGACACCGAAGCCCGGACACAGUCCCGGGGUCCGCACCGCCUGUGACCUGUGGCGGGACCGCCGGGGUGGGCGUUUUCUCAGCUGGCGCGCGCGUAGGUGGAACUUGGGAAACUAACUGGAGCGAAGUGGCAAAAAACCAAGACAGGGCCGGUGACCUCGCGCAGGCCGUCCUUAACUGUGGAGUAUUCCUUCAGCUAACCCCUUUAUUUCAUGUGUCCAAGUCUGGUUUCUGGGUUUCUUUGUAGUCCUCCGGGCCUGUUCGUGCGCCUUCACUUGCAAAAGGUUCGUCGUGGAGGGCCGUGUGCUUGUUUGCAGCAGUAACGAUGCCCUUCCCGAGCGUGCUGGAGUGGCUCCUCGCUGACGCAAGCUCACCUUGCAGCCUCCUCAGCAACUGCAACUUAAACGCGCCCUCAGGAAGCCCUGGAAUCUCGCUCAGAAUUUUUUUUCUUUUUUUGAGACAGUCUCGCUGCGACGCCCAGGCUAUAGCGCAAUGGCGCGAUCUCGGCUCCCUGCAACCUCCCUCAGGAAGCCGUGGAAGCUCGACCGCCAGAAACUUCCUUCUCCUGACUCAGGCCACAGUCUUCUGUGUGGCUGGUCUCCAGGAGGUAAGGCCCGCCCUGCAGGCAACACCGGUGCUUGGGCUCCUGCUGAGCAGUUCUUUCCUGCGAGUAACAGAACCAGGGAGGGAGGUGGGCUGUGGCCUCCCCUGCCCCUACAGUCGUCUCCUGCAGCUCCCACCAUGCUGGACUCAUCAGCAGCAGAGCAAGUGACCCGACUGACGCUGAAGCUCUUGGGACAGAAGCUGGAGCAAGAACGGCAGAACGUGGAAGGGGGACCUGAGGGCCUCCACCUCGAGCCAGGAAAUGAGGACCGGCCGGACGAUGCCCUGCAGACUGCUCUGAAGAGAAGGAGGGACCUUCUGCAGAGACUCCGGGAACAACACCUCCUGGACGAGCUCUCUCGGGCCCAGGCCUGGAGCGGGCCAAGCAGAGGAGCCCUCGGGUCAGCCCUGCCCCCAGAGCUGCCCCCCACGGGCAUCCUACCCACUGCCUCCCCAUCCCCGCUGGCCCCAGACCCGCCAAGGAUCAUCCUGCCUACGGUCCCCCAGCCUCCUGCCACCAUCAUUCAGCAGCUCCCUCAGCAGCCACUCAUAGCACAGAUUCCUCCUCCCCAGGCCUUCCCUACUCAACGGUCAGGAAGUAUUAAGGAAGACAUGGUGGAGCUGCUGCUGCUGCAGAACGCACAGGUGCACCAGUUGGUCCUGCAGAACUGGAUGCUCAAGGCCCUGCCCCCAGCCCUGCAGGACCCGCCACAUGUGCCCCCGAGGGUCCCACGAGCUGCCAGGCCAAGGCUGCCUGCCGUGCACCACCACCACCACCACCACCAUGCUGUGUGGCCACCUGGGGCUGCCACUGUCCUCCAGCCCGCCCCCAGCCUGUGGACGCCUGGCCCACCCUGAGUGUGAGUCACAGAGACCCUGGCCGGGGCACCCUCCACCCCCAGGCUUCCUCAGGGCUGUGGGCUGUGGCGGGACUAUGGAAGGGAGCAGGGAGAGACCCUGCCACCACCCGGAGUGGCUACGCGAGUGUGGACUGCAGGCUCCUCCUGGGGAAGCUGGGCAGGCUCGCUUUCUGGUCACGGGGCCAUUCCAGGGGGCAUCCCUUGCUCCGGGUCCCCUGCAGUGAGGGGCCUGUGAACCCCACCAGGGCAACAGCCCCUCCCAGGGACCCCUCCUUUCCUGUAGGGCGGCGCCGGCCCACCUGGGAGCCUCAGAUCCCCCUCUUCCAUCACGGAGGUAAAGUUGAGGCCGUGGACGCCACCAGCCUGAUGAAAUAAAGAUUUCAUCCAGAAAGAGUUUAAGAAAAUCUCAGCUCAGGAGCCAGAACAGAAAAGAUCAAUAGCUUUAGCCACAUGGAAGUGUGAACAUCCUGAUGGGGAAAAUACCACAAAGUCUAAUUUAAUAACUAGGGACACCUGUGUCCACAGCUGUGGCACAGACUCCCACUAAAGAAGUAGGGGUGCAUGGCUCAUGCCUGUAAUCCCAGCACUUUAAGAGGCUGAGGCAGGAGGAUCACUUGAGCUCAGGAAUUCGAGACCAGCCUGGGUCACAUAGCAAGACCCCGUCUCUACAAAAAAUAAAUUUAAAAAACUAGCCAGGUGUGGUGAUAUGCGCCUGUUAUCUCAGCAGCUCUGGGGGCUGAGGUGGGAGGAUUGCUUGAGCCCAGGAGUUAGAAGCUGCAGUGAGCUCUGAUGGAACCACUGCACUAUAGCCUGGACCACAGAGCAGGCCCCUGUCUCAAAAAUAAAAUAAAAAAGUGAAAGAAGCAA